GUUGUCAACAGCCCAGAAAGAGAAAGACGGAGAGGCAGAGACCCAGGGGAGCCGAGGAGCGGAGACACGGACCCAGCAGGGUCACGCGGGAGGAGACUCGGGACACCCACUCGCUGGCUGCCACCGGGAGCAGAGGGGGGCUCGGCCGCCCCCUCCCACAUCAGUCUCCAGACCCUUGGGGCUUCAGAGGCCGCUCCUAGGCUCCUCGGAGGAGGCGCGGGUUUCUUCUUUUCCGGAGAGCAAACUUUCCUCGGAGAUGCCUGGCAGGAUGAGCCGCGGCCCCCGGAGAGGACGGGACAGCCUCUGAUCGCCGCCUGCGUGCCCCGCCACUGCCCAUGGCCAGGAGGCCCCAGGGAACGGACAGCCCGACCUCUUAGGCGCCGGGACCCUCAGGCUCAGAUCAGUGGCCGAGGCCCCAGAGUUUGCAAACUCAGCUCUGGAGUUCAGCAGCAACAGCAGCAGGAAAAACCUGCCCCUGCUCCCCCCUCCCGCCACCUCCCCUCUCCUCUUCUCCCCUCACCCAGCAGGCACCCCCGGUUCCCGCCAGGCCCUCCUGCCAUGUCGGACCCAGACGUCCCCAGGGGCUCGGAUGUCCCCGCCAUGUGGCCCCCUUGUUCCAGGGGUGCCUGAGCCCCUUCAAGGAGCCCCAACCCACCCCCAACCUUGGCCCAGCCCUGAGCCCCAGGGACCAUGAGCGGGGGCAAGAAGAAGAGUAGUUUCCAAAUCACCAGCGUCACCACGGACUAUGAGGGCCCUGGGAGCCCAGGGGCUUCGGAUCCCCCUACCCCACAGCCCCCAACCGGGCCCCCGCCCCGCCUGCCCAAUGGGGAGCCCAGCCCCGAUCCGGGGGGCAAGGGCACCCCCCGGAAUGGCUCCCCACCACCUGGGGCCCCUUCCUCCCGUUUCCGGGUGGUGAAGCUGCCCCACGGCCUGGGAGAGCCUUAUCGCCGCGGUCGCUGGACGUGUGUGGAUGUUUAUGAGCGAGACCUGGAGCCCCACAGCUUCGGCGGACUCCUGGAGGGAAUUCGAGGGGCCUCAGGGGGCGCCGGGGGCAGAUCUUUGGAUUCCAGGUUGGAGCUGGCCAGCCUCGGCCUGGGCGCCCCCACCCCACCGUCAGGCCUGUCUCAGGGCCCCACCUCCUGGCUCCGUCCACCCCCCACCUCUCCUGGACCUCAGGCCCGCUCCUUCACUGGGGGACUGGGCCAGCUGGUGGUGCCCAGCAAAGCCAAGGCAGAGAAACCCCCACUGUCGGCCUCCUCACCCCAGCAGCGCCCCCCAGAGCCUGAGACCGGUGAGAGUGCGGGCACAUCCCGGGCUGCCACGCCCCUGCCCUCUCUGAGGGUGGAAGCGGAGGCUGGGGGCUCAGGGGCCAGGACCCCUCCACUGUCCCGGAGGAAAGCUGUAGACAUGCGGCUGCGGAUGGAGUUGGGUGCUCCAGAAGAGAUGGGGCAGGUGCCCCCACUUGACUCUCGCCCCAGCUCCCCAGCCCUCUACUUCACCCACGAUGCCAGCCUGGUUCACAAAUCUCCAGACCCCUUCGGAGCAGUAGCAGCUCAGAAGUUCAGCCUGGCCCACUCCAUGUUGGCCAUCAGUGGUCACCUAGACAGCGACGAUGAUAGUGGCUCCGGAAGCCUGGUUGGCAUUGACAACAAAAUCGAGCAAGCCAUGGUUUUCUUCUGGAGGCAAAAAAUUAAACCAACCAUCUCAGGACACCCUGACUCCAAGAAACACUCAUUGAAGAAGAUGGAGAAGACUCUCCAGGUGGUUGAGACUUUGAGGUUGGUCGAGCUCCCAAAAGAGGCUAAGCCCAAGUUGGGUGAGUCCCCCGAGCUGGCAGAUCCCUGCGUGUUGGCCAAGACUACAGAGGAGACCGAGGUGGAGCUGGGCCAACAGGGCCAAUCCCUACUGCAGCUGCCGAGGACGGCCGUCAAGUCUGUCUCCACGCUCAUGGUCUCUGCCCUGCAGAGCGGCUGGCAGAUGUGCAGCUGGAAGUCAUCAGUGAGUUCUGCCUCAGUCAGCUCCCAAGUGAGGACGCAGUCACCUUUGAAGACUCCGGAGGCUGAGUUGCUGUGGGAGGUGUACCUGGUGCUGUGGGCCGUUCGGAAACACCUGCGCCGGCUGUACCGCAGGCAGGAGAGGCACAGACGGCACCACGUCCGAUGCCAUGCUGCCCCCCGACCCAACCCGGCUCAGUCCCUGAAACUGGAUGCCCAAAGUCCCCUCUAGGGGGAACCCCAGACCCUUAGAGAGUCCUGACCUCACUCUUACCUGGGGUCCCAUAUCAGCCCCUUCAUUCCAUGUAUUCCAGUUGUAAAACAAGUAUCAAAAUAUUGGGAAAUAAAUAUCAGAUAGUUCUGA